AUUCUCGCUAGUUCGAUCGGUAGCGGGAGCGGAGAGCGGACCCCAGAGAGCCCUGAGCAGCCCCACCGCCGCCGCCGGCCUAGUUACCAUCACACCCCGGGAGGAGCCGCAGCUGCCGCAGCCGGCCCCAGUCACCAUCACCGCAACCAUGAGCAGCGAGGCCGAGACCCAGCAGCCGCCCGCCGCCCCCCCCGCCGCCCCCGCCCUCAGCGCCGCCGACACCAAGCCCGGCACUACGGGCAGCGGCGCAGGGAGCGGUGGCCCGGGCGGCCUCACAUCGGCGGCGCCUGCCGGCGGGGACAAGAAGGUCAUCGCAACGAAGGUUUUGGGAACAGUAAAAUGGUUCAAUGUAAGGAACGGAUAUGGUUUCAUCAACAGGAAUGACACCAAGGAAGAUGUAUUUGUACACCAGACUGCCAUAAAGAAGAAUAACCCCAGGAAGUACCUUCGCAGUGUAGGAGAUGGAGAGACUGUGGAGUUUGAUGUUGUUGAAGGAGAAAAGGGUGCGGAGGCAGCAAAUGUUACAGGUCCUGGUGGUGUUCCAGUUCAAGGCAGUAAAUAUGCAGCAGACCGUAACCAUUAUAGACGCUAUCCACGUCGUAGGGGUCCUCCACGCAAUUACCAGCAAAAUUACCAGAAUAGUGAGAGUGGGGAAAAGAACGAGGGAUCGGAGAGUGCUCCCGAAGGCCAGGCCCAACAACGCCGGCCCUACCGCAGGCGAAGGUUCCCACCUUACUACAUGCGGAGACCCUAUGGGCGUCGACCACAGUAUUCCAACCCUCCUGUGCAGGGAGAAGUGAUGGAGGGUGCUGACAACCAGGGUGCAGGAGAACAAGGUAGACCAGUGAGGCAGAAUAUGUAUCGGGGAUAUAGACCACGAUUCCGCAGGGGCCCUCCUCGCCAAAGACAGCCUAGAGAGGACGGCAAUGAAGAAGAUAAAGAAAAUCAAGGAGAUGAGACCCAAGGUCAGCAGCCACCUCAACGUCGGUACCGCCGCAACUUCAAUUACCGACGCAGACGCCCAGAAAACCCUAAACCACAAGAUGGCAAAGAGACAAAAGCAGCCGAUCCACCAGCUGAGAAUUCGUCCGCUCCCGAGGCUGAGCAGGGCGGGGCUGAGUAAAUGCCGGCUUACCAUCUCUACCAUCAUCCGGUUUAGUCAUCCAACAAGAAGAAAUAUGAAAUUCCAGCAAUAAGAAAUGAACAAAAGAUUGGAGCUGAAGACCUAAAGUGCUUGCUUUUUGCCCGUUGACCAGAUAAAUAGAACUAUCUGCAUUAUCUAUGCAGCAUGGGGUUUUUAUUAUUUUUACCUAAAGACGUCUCUUUUUGGUAAUAACAAACGUGUUUUUUAAAAAAGCCUGGUUUUUCUCAAUACGCCUUUAAAGGUUUUUAAAUUGUUUCAUAUCUGGUCAAGUUGAGAUUUUUAAGAACUUCAUUUUUAAUUUGUAAUAAAAGUUUACAACUUGAUUUUUUCAAAAAAGUCAACAAACUGCAAGCACCUGUUAAUAAAGGUCUUAAAUAAUUGUCUUUGUGUAAAUUUGUCUAGUUUUGCUUUAGUUUGUAAGUAUUUAGCUAUUUAUAGGACCCUUAGCUUGACCCAGUCUACAAAUAGAUGAUGCUCACUGGUAAUUCCCUCAGGUAAAAUGUCUCAAAAUCUCUAAUCCUUUAAGUGGCAUGCCUGUGGGCCCAUACUAAAAAUUAGAAAAUACAUACUCUGAUAACCUGGCCAUUUUUCAUUGAAGGAUUUAGCUCAUUUGUAAGAAAGACUUGAGUGUAGAUUUUGGGUGGGUCCCUUUGGCUGUGAGGCAUUGUUUAAAAGGGCAUUGCUCUAGCCUAGACCGACCAGACUCUCAUCCUGCUCCACUUAGUUUUGUCACCUUGGGAGAAUUUGUUUCAGUGUGUCAAUUGAAGAUGCCAAUUGAAGUGUUAGGACAACCUGUCACACUGCCUGGUGUGGUCAUCAAAUAUUGGUUCAGCUCCUUAUGUCCUAGAGAUGGAAACAAGUAAUAUAAAACCCAUGGGAAAGCUGCUUAGGAACAUGGAGGUUGGUGAGCUUGUAAUUAUGUGGUUCUCAACACCUUAAAUCCUAAGCCUAGUCUGGCUGAUCUUUUCUCUUUUUGAGACGGAGUCUUGUUCUGUCAUCAGGCUGGAGUACAGUGGCACAAUCUUGGCUCACUGCAACCUCCACCUCUAGGUUUAAGCGAUUCUCCUGCCUCGGCCACCUUAGUAGCUGGGAGUACAGGUGCGUGCCACCACACCCAGCUAAUUUUUGUAUUUUUAAUAGAGAUGGGGUUGCACUGUGUUAGCCAGGAUGGUCUUGAUCUCUUGACCUUGUGAUCCGCCCGCCUCAGCCUCCCAAAGUGCUGGGAUUACAGGUGUGAGCCACCGCACCUGGCCUCUCUGGCUUUUGUUUUCUAAUGUUUUGUUAGAUGUUCUUUGGCUUGCUUUGUGAAAUAGUCAUGUAGUUGAUAGUGACUGCUGCCCCGAAACACUCCAGAUCAUCCUGGCCAGCUAUCAGGGCCCAGGGGAAGCAGACAGUAGGGGUCGGGAGUAGGCCAGAGUGGCACAUCAGGAAUCCUGCAGUGCUGUGGAAGUCAUCUCCUGCUUGGGACUAACUCUUUGCAGAGGACUUGAUAAGAGACUACUCAAAAAAAAUUUUUUUAACCCUACUUAGUGUAAAUAUCUGUACUGCAGAAGUGAGUUAGCCUAUUUCUUGCUGGUGUUCAUGAAAAUACUGUGUUGGCAAGAGUGCAGUGGACCUGAAACUUCAACUGUUGGUAGCAUCUAAACUGUUACUUACAACUGCAGACGCACACAGUCCCUGACUUAAACAGUGGUUUGACUUAGGGGCUUUUAGUGGGGUUACGGUUUCUACUGAAUCAACAUUGUUUUCAUGGCAUCACAGAGUUGAAAAAUCAUAAAUGAAACCAUUGUAAGUUGACUGCAGUGUUGCCAACAUUAAAUGCAGUUUCAACUUAA